AGAAUAAAAUAAUUAAAUAGUUGACCUUUGGCAGAGUCUUUGUUGAAAUAGGCAAGGGUUUUGAGCUUCUCAGAACUUGAGACCAUUGCCUUCUGGAGUCUUUCCUCAGAUGAGUCUGUGCCUCCUUCUAGCUAGUGCACUCUGAGCACUGUGGCCACAUCUGGAGGGUGGAGAGGAGACUUAGCUUCCAAUGGUGGUCACUCUAGGGGAGGGGGGCCCUUGCAAAUACCAAAAUUUUUUUAAAUUAUUAUUUUAUGAGCUUUUAAAAACUUUUUUGUUUUUGUCAUCACAAAAGUAAUAAACACUUGUGAUAAAUUCAGACAACACUGAAGUGCUUUAACAUAAGCAACAAAAUCUUCUGUGACCUCCCCCAACCUUUUCCAACCAUUCCCCAAACAUAAGCACUUUUGAGAGUUUGCUUCUUAUACUCCUGGACUUUUGCAUUUGCUUGUUUCUCUCCACCCCUACCCUUUGCCCUCAACCACGACAUAGAUACUUUCCCUUUUGUUUUCUAAAGAUAGACUGUCCCUGUGCAUGGUGUUCUGCAACUUUCUUUUUACAGCUGUCAAUUAUUAUGGUUAUUUUUCCAAGUCCAUAUGUACAGAUAAAUGUACUUGUUACUUUUAAAAGUUGUACUCCAUGUUAUGGUUGUAUGUUAAGUAAAUUUCGUUUUGUAUUGAUAGACACUCAGGUUGUUUCUGACCUUUUGCCAUUGCAGUCAUUGCUGCUGUGGAAAUUUUUGUGCACACGUGUGAACUUUUGCCUGAGAUUUUCUUUGGUAUAGAUACAUAGAAGUAGGACUUUUGGUUUAAAUGGUUUGCUGUUUAAAAUUUGAAUCCAUAAUGCCAAAUUACCCUCCAAAAAGGCUGUACCAAUUCAUGCUCUUCCUAGGAGCAUCCCAUUAUGGCUUUGCUAAUCUAGUUUUUGCUUACACAUGUGUAAGAAAGUAAAUCUUAAAAGCCUCACAAAUAAUGCCAUCAAAAUUACACGUUUAUCUUAGAAAAGCAUUCAGAAUAUAUGUCUGUAGAUUUAAUUAUAUGAUUUUUAUAUCUUGACUUUGAUGGUGGUUAUCAUCCUGCAAGGUGACAAAAAGUUCCCUAAAUACUGUACACAAUUAUUAAAUAAUUAUUAAGGAUAUCAGUUGUGCCAGGUAGCCUUUGGAAGAAUUACAGCCAAAUCACAGCUUCCUUUUCCACAGCUCUGCCAGGCUGGCUUGUCUUUCCCACCAAGGGCUGAGCCAUUAAUACUGAGGCUGGGUCAGCAUUUGAAGGGGCCCUGCCAGGGAGUGCCAGGCCUUGGGCCCCAGAGACCUGGGGAGUGGGAGAUGGCAAGUGACUGCUGUGAGGCUGAGACAAAGUUUUUGCCUACAACACCCCAUGGCUGUUUCCUUUACUGAGCUAGAUGAGGAAAGCAAAGGGAAGUGAUGGUCCAAGACUUCUGGUGGUCACUUUUGUUCAUAGAUUUCUCACAGGAGUGCUAACAUUUAGGCUCAUGUUUACGAAGGUUUGAAACCUUAGCAUUUGGGAAGGAUCUGCAAAUUCUCAGCCAGGGGCCUUAACUGAUCACAGGUAGUUGUGAACUCUUGGUCCAGGCUGUAUCUCAAGGCUUCUUCUUAGAAGGACAGGUCAGCUUACCACCUGCUAACUGCAUGUGAAAUUUUGAAUUCUGCCUUCUCUAGCUCUCCUCUCUGGCUCUGAGCUGGUAUCUGGCAUUUGCAAACAGUUUACCCUUUGUUGACUUCUUAGCACUAACCUCACUUUUAUGAGUCUGAGUAGACUUGAUACCCAGGCCAUUUAUCCUUUGAGGGUGCCCUCAGCUUCAUCAGACCCAUGCUGGGCAGUCUGGCAUAGUGGUAAGAGGCACUUGGAGCCAGACAGACCUGGGUUCAAAUCCUGACAUCAUCACAUUUACUAACAGUGUGACCCUUUGGCUGAUGACCUCACCUCUUUGAGCAUCAGUGUCUCCUUCUACAAAGUAGGGACAGUAAUUCUUUCCCAGGGGUAUUUUGAAGGAUAUACGAAUUAAUAUUUGUCAGGUGCCUCUCAGAUGUUCAGCACAAAAUAAACAGUGUAUAAAUAUGAGUCCUCUCUUAUCUUCCUGCUGUAGAGAGAAAGUUCGUUGGGGAUGCUCCAAGUUGGUGGCUACUGGCUGAGGAUCCUGGAGUAAGAGGAAGGCUACCAUGUAAACCCAGAGAUGAAUCAUGAACAAUGUGUAUUCUCAGGAGCUUAGUAUUUGAUAUGGGAGCCUAACAAGCAAAUAGUGUGUCCAGUAAUAGGAACUGAUUAAUAGAGGAAAGAUUAAUUAACCUUCUAGGUGGGUGGGGUGGAAAAGUAGGUGGGGUAUUGAAGGUUCAACAGGAGUUCGACAGAGAAGAUAGACCAUAAAUAAUAAAUAUACGGCUGUAUCCACUAGAGAUAAAGUUACAUUGUUUUUUAUGUACAUGUUGACUUCUUUUGGCCUUGCCAAUGCACUGAUAUAUUCAAAUUCAGCUCCUCUCUUUUUCUCUUCCCUUUUCCCUUCACUCUGCCUUUCCUCCAGCCCUGCCUUGAAAUACUCAGCCACUGAAAAUUUCUUAAAGAAUUUCUUUAUACUUUAGUAAGUCCUCAGAGGAUACCAGUUCACCCUACUGAGAUUUUACAAGAACUUUGGUGUAGCUGGGGUUUUUUUUGCAUUCCUUUUUCUACGGUAGAUAUAAGUUCUUUUGGGUUGCCCAUCAAUGAACAAACUACCAACCAUUUGAUGUUUACUGCGUGACUCCUGUAUACCAAGCACAUGUGCCAUUUCACUUAGUCCCCAGAAUGUCAGAGCAGCUUUGUGAAAUGGGCUGCCCGUUCUUUCUUAUGGAUGAAGAAACUGAGGCUUAGGUAGGUUAAUAUACUGAAUAUUAUACAUGUAGUGAGUGGGAAAGCCACAGUUCACCUCCAGGGUCUUUUUCUCCCUCUUUGCUGCCUUGCUUGGGGUCCUGCUCAUAGUAGGUGGACAGCAGAUGUUUGUCUGAACAUAUGAGAACACUGCCUGCCACGUGCCGGUCAGUUUGAUUUGUGCUGCUGGUUUUGUAACCCACAUGGGGCAAUGACAGCUGCUCAGGUACUUUCCUACCUAUUAGUGGGGCCCCAGGGUCACACAUCAGUCAUAAUUGACAAAAAACACAAUUUCCCUUUCCUCUCAACUUUUAUUUCUAAGGUACUUGUAAGCAGGUAGAUUAGAUUGUUAACUUUUCAUUUUUUGCUUUGUCUCUCUCCUUUAAAGACUAUGUGAAAGAAUACACAGUGCCCUGAGAGCCUGGCCUGGGAAUCAGAAACUUAGAUUCCAGCUUCGGUUCUGCUGGUAACUCCUCAGUCAUUAUGGGUUCCGAUGUCAUAGGAAUCUACGCUAGAGGGCUUCCUGUGUGCCGGGCACUGUGGUUUUUGGAAGAAGCUGACCGCCUGAAAAGAAAUUAUAAAACAUGAAAAUCGCUUUGAGGUGACCAAGUCCAGAGGCCCCUAACUCCUCCCAAGCUGGAUCUGGGGUGUAAGAACUGUGACUUCAGAUCAUCCAAUGGCAGACCAGAGAAUGGACAUUUCUUCAACCAUCAGUGAUUUCAUGUCCCCGGGCCCCACCGACCUGCUUUCCAGCUCUCUUGGUACCAGUGGUGUGGAUUGCAACCGCAAACGGAAAGGCAGCUCCACUGACUACCAAGAAAGCAUGGACACAGACAAAGAUGACCCUCAUGGAAGGUUAGAAUAUACAGAACACCAAGGAAGGAUAAAAAAUGCAAGGGAAGCUCACAGUCAGAUUGAAAAGCGGCGUCGGGAUAAAAUGAACAGUUUUAUAGAUGAAUUGGCUUCUUUGGUACCAACAUGCAACGCAAUGUCCAGGAAAUUAGAUAAACUUACUGUGCUAAGGAUGGCUGUUCAGCACAUGAAAACAUUAAGAGGUGCCACCAAUCCAUACACAGAAGCAAACUACAAACCAACUUUUCUAUCAGACGAUGAAUUGAAACACCUCAUUCUCAGGGCAGCAGAUGGAUUUUUGUUUGUCGUAGGAUGUGACCGAGGGAAGAUACUCUUUGUCUCAGAGUCUGUCUUCAAGAUCCUCAACUACAGCCAGAAUGAUCUGAUUGGUCAGAGUUUGUUUGACUACCUGCAUCCUAAAGAUAUUGCCAAAGUCAAGGAGCAGCUCUCCUCCUCUGACACCGCACCCCGGGAGCGGCUCAUAGAUGCAAAAACUGGACUUCCAGUUAAAACAGAUAUAACCCCUGGGCCAUCUCGAUUAUGUUCUGGAGCACGACGUUCUUUCUUCUGUAGGAUGAAGUGUAACAGGCCUUCAGUAAAGGUUGAAGACAAGGACUUCCCCUCUACCUGCUCAAAGAAAAAAGCAGAUCGAAAAAGCUUCUGCACAAUCCACAGCACAGGCUAUUUGAAAAGCUGGCCACCCACAAAGAUGGGGCUGGAUGAAGACAACGAACCAGACAAUGAGGGGUGUAACCUCAGCUGCCUCGUCGCAAUUGGACGACUGCAUUCUCAUGUAGUUCCACAACCAGUGAACGGGGAAAUCAGGGUGAAAUCUAUGGAAUAUGUUUCUCGGCACGCGAUAGAUGGAAAGUUUGUUUUUGUAGACCAGAGGGCAACAGCUAUUUUGGCAUAUUUACCACAAGAACUUCUAGGCACAUCGUGUUAUGAAUAUUUUCACCAAGAUGACAUAGGACAUCUUGCAGAAUGUCAUAGGCAAGUUUUACAGACGAGAGAAAAAAUUACAACUAAUUGCUAUAAAUUUAAAAUCAAAGAUGGUUCUUUUAUCACACUACGGAGUCGAUGGUUCAGUUUCAUGAACCCUUGGACCAAGGAAGUAGAAUAUAUUGUCUCAACUAACACUGUUGUUUUAGCCAACGUCCUGGAAGGCGGGGACCCAACCUUCCCACAGCUCACAGCAUCCCCCCACAGCAUGGACAGCAUGCUGCCCUCUGGAGAAGAUUCCUUUGUUGUAGGUGGCCCAAAGAGGACCCACCCCACUGUUCCAGGGAUUCCAGGGGGAACCCGGGCUGGGGCAGGAAAAAUAGGCCGAAUGAUUGCUGAGGAAAUCAUGGAAAUCCACAGGAUAAGAGGGUCAUCGCCUUCUAGCUGUGGCUCCAGCCCAUUGAACAUCACGAGUACGCCUCCCCCUGAUGCCUCUUCUCCAGGAGGCAAGAAGAUUUUAAAUGGAGGGACUCCAGACAUUCCUUCCAGUGGCCUACUAUCAGGCCAGGCUCAGGAGAACCCAGGUUAUCCAUAUUCUGAUAGUUCUUCUAUUCUUGGUGAGAACCCCCACAUAGGUAUAGACAUGAUUGACAACGACCAAGGAUCAAGUAGUCCCAGUAAUGAUGAGGCAGCAAUGGCUGUCAUCAUGAGCCUCUUGGAAGCAGAUGCUGGACUGGGUGGCCCUGUUGACUUUAGUGACUUGCCAUGGCCGCUGUAAACACUACAUGUUGCUUUGGCAACAGCUAUAGUAUCAAAGUGCAUUACUGGUGGAGUUUUACAGUCUGUGAAGCUUACUGGAUAAGGAGAGAAUAGCUUUUAUGUACUGACUUCAUAAAAGCCAUCUCAGAGCCAUUGAUACAAGUCAAUCUUACUAUAUGUAACUUCAGACAAAGUGGAACUAAGCCUGCUCCAGUGUUUCCUCAUCAUUGAUUAUUGGGCUAGCUGUGGAUAGCUUGCAUUAAUUGUAUAUUUUGGAUUCUGUUUGUGUUGAAUUUUUUAAUCAUUGUGCACAGAAGCAUCAUUGGUAGCUUUUAUAUGCAAAUGGUCAUUUCAGAUGUAUGGUGUUUUUACACUACAAAGAAGUCCCCCAUGUGGAUAUUUCUUAUACUAAUUGUAUCAUAAAGCCGUUUAUUCUUCCUUGUAAGAAUCCUUUACUAUAAAUAUGGGUUAAAGUAUAAUGUACUAGACAGUUAAAUAUUUUUAAUAAAUGUUUCCCUUGUUCUAUAAA